AGUCGCGGGGCGGCGGCGGCGGCUGCGGGCGCGAGGUGAGGGGCGCGAGGUGAGGGUCGCGAGGUUCCCAGCAGGAUGCCCCGGCUCUGCAGGAAGCUGAAGUGAGAGGCCCGGAGAGGGCCCAGCCCGCCCGGGGCAGGAUGACCAAGGCCCGGCUGUUCCGGCUGUGGCUGGUGCUGGGGUCGGUGUUCAUGAUCCUGCUGAUCAUCGUGUACUGGGACAGCGCAGGCGCCGCGCACUUCUACUUGCACACGUCCUUCUCUAGGCCGCACACGGGGCCGCCGCUGCCCACGCCCGGGCCGGACAGGGACAGGGAGCUCACGGCCGACUCCGAUGUCGACGAGUUUCUGGACAAGUUUCUCAGUGCUGGCGUGAAGCAGAGCGACCUUCCCAGAAAGGAGACGGAGCAGCCGCCUGCGCCGGGGAGCAUGGAGGAGAGCGUGAGAGGCUACGACUGGUCCCCGCGCGACGCCCGGCGCAGCCCAGACCAGGGCCGGCAGCAGGCGGAGCGGAGGAGCGUGCUGCGGGGCUUCUGCGCCAACUCCAGCCUGGCCUUCCCCACCAAGGAGCGCGCAUUCGACGACAUCCCCAACUCGGAGCUGAGCCACCUGAUCGUGGACGACCGGCACGGGGCCAUCUACUGCUACGUGCCCAAGGUGGCCUGCACCAACUGGAAGCGCGUGAUGAUCGUGCUGAGCGGAAGCCUGCUGCACCGCGGUGCGCCCUACCGCGACCCGCUGCGCAUCCCGCGCGAGCACGUGCACAACGCCAGCGCGCACCUGACCUUCAACAAGUUCUGGCGCCGCUACGGGAAGCUCUCCCGCCACCUCAUGAAGGUCAAGCUCAAGAAGUACACCAAGUUCCUCUUCGUGCGCGACCCCUUCGUGCGCCUGAUCUCCGCCUUCCGCAGCAAGUUCGAGCUGGAGAACGAGGAGUUCUACCGCAAGUUCGCCGUGCCCAUGCUGCGGCUGUACGCCAACCACACCAGCCUGCCCGCCUCGGCGCGCGAGGCCUUCCGCGCUGGCCUCAAGGUGUCCUUCGCCAACUUCAUCCAGUACCUGCUGGACCCGCACACGGAGAAGCUGGCGCCCUUCAACGAGCACUGGCGGCAGGUGUACCGCCUCUGCCACCCGUGCCAGAUCGACUACGACUUCGUGGGGAAGCUGGAGACUCUGGACGAGGACGCCGCGCAGCUGCUGCAGCUACUCCAGGUGGACCGGCAGCUCCGCUUCCCCCCGAGCUACCGGAACAGGACCGCCAGCAGCUGGGAGGAGGACUGGUUCGCCAAGAUCCCCCUGGCCUGGAGGCAGCAGCUGUAUAAACUCUACGAGGCCGACUUUGUUCUCUUCGGCUACCCCAAGCCCGAAAACCUCCUCCGAGACUGAAAGCUUUCGCGUUGCUUUUUCUCGCGUGCCUGGAACCUGACGCACGCGCACUCCAGUUUUUUUAUGACCUACGAUUUUGCAAUCUGGGCUUCUUGUUCACUCCACUGCCUCUAUCCAUUGAGUACUGUAUCGAUAUUGUUUUUUAAGAUUAAUAUAUUUCAGGUAUUUAAUACGAAAUGUGGAAGGGAAUGCUGGAGUAAAAUAUCCCCUCUCCCCUCCGCCCGCCCACCCGCCCGCCCGCUCGCCCGCUCGCCCGCUCCUGUGGUUUUUCUGAGCGUGCGGGCGCCGGGAGGGGAUGCUGAGGCUGAUGGAGCUGCCUCCAGGGCUAGGGCCACUCACCGGAGGAGGGCGGGGCCUGCACUUGAAGUCAGGCCGCACCUGUCUGUUUUUGGAAGGGUAGCCGACAAAUCCUUCCAGAGGGAAAGUUCUUUGUUUAAGUGUUGUACUUGAAAAGGUCAAUCUUCAGGGCUUCCUGUUUGAAGUCAAGUCAGAGGUAAACCGGUCAGUUACAGAAGCAGGAUUUCUAGGAUUUCUAACUCCAGCUGUUCCCAUACUGUCUAGUUUAAAUUAUGGCUGUUAAGGCCGGGCGGGUGACUCAGGCAGGUAAUCCCAGAACUUUGGGAGGCCCAGACAGAAGGAUCGCUUGAGGUCAGGAAUUUGAGACCUGGCCAACAUGGUGAAACCCUGUCUCUACUAAAAAAAAAAAAAAAAAAAAAAAAAAAAAAAAAAAAAUGAGUCGGGUGUGGUGGUGUGCACCUGUAGUCCCAGCUACUCAGGAGUUCUGAGAUGGAAAGAUUGCUUGAACCCAGGAGGCAGAGGCUGCAGUGAGCUGAGAUCGCGACAUUGCACUCUAGCCUGGGUGACAGAGUGAGAUUCCAUCUCAAAAUAAAUAAAUAAAUAUUAAUACAUUAUGGCUAUUAAGGCUGGGCACGGUGGCUCAUGCCUGCAAUCCUGGCACUUUGGGAGGCUGAGGGGGGAAGAUCACUUGAGCCCAGGAGUUCAAGACCAGCUUGGGCAACAUAGCAAGGACCUCAUCUCUACAAAAAAUAAAAAGGACGUGGUGGUGCACAUCUGUAAACCCAGCUACUCAGGAGGCUGAGGAGGGAGGAUCACUUGAGCCCAGGAGUUCAAGAUCAGUUUGGACCACAUAGCGAGACCCUGUGUCUACAAAAAAUAAGAAAAUCAGCCGGACAUGAUGGUGCACACCUGUAAUCCCAGCUACUCGGGAGGCUGAGGCAGGAGGAUCGCUGGAGCCCAGGAGUUCAAGGCUGCAGUGACCUAUGAUCGUGCCACUGCACUCCAGCCUGGGCAGCAAAGUGAGACUCUGUUUCUAAAUAGACAGAUAGAAGAUAGGUAGAUAGAUAGAUUAAAUAGAAAGUAAACUAUGGCUGUUGAGGUUUACAGUUGGCAGGAGUGGAGUGGUUUGGCGUUUAUCUCUAGACCGUGCUGGAUGACAGUACCCAGUGUCACCAAGAAGAGGCUCCGUGUGACUGUCUCUGUGGCUUUCUGGUUGGUUUAGCUCCAGUGCCUUCACCCUCAAGGACACGACUGACCUUGAACCCUCAGGUUUGAUGGGCCCUGUCUUGAUAAAAGUGUCAGAGGAGGCUCUGGAAACAUCUGGCUGAAACUCCUUUGCUAUUUCUGCUUCUAAGCUGUAGUUGGAGAGAUGGUUGCAAUCAUUUCGUGGUGUCGGGCACCCUGCUUGACCUGUCUUCCUCGUGUGUGGUAUUUGUCACCACUGCCCAGUCCCUGGUUGCUGGCCACGCUCAGUUGGGACAUACCCUGGUGUCCUCUGUGUGUGGUGUCCCUGUGUUUCCCAGGCUCAGGUGGGCUUGUGUGGGUCUUGGCCCCCAGUGCCUGCUAGCCUCAGGUGUCCCCUGUGUUAGACACCUCCUGCCUUCCUUUCUGAAGCUUCGCUUUCUUUUAUUUUUGUUUUGUUUUGUUUUUGGAGACAGGGUCUCGCUCUGUCAUCCGGGCUGGAAUACACUGGUGCAAUCACAGCUCACUGCAGCUUCAACCUCCUGGGCUCAAGUGAUCUUCCCAUCUCAGACUCCCAAGUAGCUGGGGUUACAGGUGAGCGCCAGCCUGCCCAGCUAGUUUUUUAUUUUCAGCAGAGAUGAGGUCUCACUGUGUUGCCCAGGCUGCUCUCAAACUCCUGGGCUCAAGUGACCCUCCUGCAUCACCCUCCCAAAGUGCUGGGAUUACAGGCAUGAGCCAUCACACCUGGCCCCUCCAAGUUUUUUAUUAUGAUAAAAAUGUUUAAUUUUAAACGUACCAUCUUAACCAUUGUUAAGUGCACUGUUGUGUGGCAUUAAGCACAUUCGUAUUGUCGUGCCACCACCACCAUCAUCUCCAGAGCUUUCUCAUCUUCCCAAACUGAAACUCUGUCCCCAUUCAGCACUCGCUCCCCAUUGGUAGAAGGCAGCAGCUUCCACUCUCUGAUUUCUACUACCCGAGCUCCCUCAGAAAUGGAGUCACACAGUAUUGGUCCUUUUGGGACUGAAGUACUUCACCUCAUGCAAUGUCCUCUAGGUUCAUCGGUGUCGUGGCAGGUGUCAGAACUAACUUCCUUUCUGAGGCGGAAUAAUGUCCCAUUGUGUGGAAGAGGCAUGGUUUGUUUAUCUGUUCAUCAGUUGGUGGACACUGAGUUGCUUCUGCCUUCCUGCGAAUGUGAAUUGAAUGCUGCUGUGAACAGGGUGUCAGUGAAUCUGCUGAGGGCUUGUUUUCCGUAUUCUGGGCAUGGCCCUUUGUGUCUGCCUUUGCUGGAGCACCUCCCCGGGAUGCGUUUGUUUAUAGGAUGUUCAGACGAAUGUCAGAACCCACUGGGCGGUUCACUCACUGAGGGGGGCCCGCGUCCCCUCCAUUUCUGCAUUCCCAGUUCUUGGUAUGGUUCCUCUGAGGUUCGGUUUUCCUGAGCACCUGGGGUGUUUGCAGGGAUGUGGAGGGGUUCCUGCAGAAGACACCACCCACAUCCACGCACCUGCUCAGAUUCCCGGGCCAUGGUCGGGGCCACCGCCCGUGGGGAUGACUCCGGAUGGGAGUGGCAGAAAAGGGCCUGCUGGGCCGAGGGGAGGCGUCUCCGGGAAGAGAGGGAGGUGUGAGCGGGGAGAACCCACUUUGAUUCUUCGCUGUUUGCCUGAUGCGCAGCACCACACUGCGUAGAGACCUUUGGCUCUGGUUUUUUCUUUUUCCACUGAAACACAGCAAAUUAUACAUUUUAUGAAAAUUGGCAUCGUACAACUGGAAAAUUUAACCAUAAACUUAAAACUCUUUUACCCUGUUGGCCCCCAUCCUCCAGCUGUGUCCACACUUUGAGCACAGUCAUGAGAAUGACUUGGUUGGGUGCGGGGUGGUGUCACAAAGCCCUGUCUCUUGUGUGAUGGCUGCGCCUCGAAUCAGUGGGAGGGCACCUCGCCCGUUUACAGUUGGGCAAUGCUUGGGCUGGGCGGCCUGGCUGCUCCUGGACUCGCCUCCCAGCGUCUGAUGCUGUGUAUUUUCCAUCUGCCCCAGGAAUUUGACACAGGUGUGACUUGCAGGUUGUGUGGGUGAUGCCUCCCUCCCUCUUUCCUCUUAAAGCAUCUCAUGCUUCUUCAUUCGCUGAUACUUACAACCCCCAGUGGAUAUUUAGUGGAGUUUGCUGUAGUGCUUUUGCCAUUUAUUUGGACUAUUGGAAAAAUUUCAGGUUUGGUUUUGGCCCUAUGUCUUGAUGGAGGGCAAGGGUUAGGAUUUCAGUUUAUCUUCCCGGUGAGGUCUGAGCACGUCUGUGCCCUGAGGUGGGUGGUUUGGUGAAGGUGGGGCUUUAACCUAGCUCUGCCACUUAGGAAUCAGAACACACACACACACGCGCGCACACACACACACACACACACACUCUCUCUCACACACACAUCGGGAUAUUUUUCUUGUUUCCUUCUUCCAGAGGGUGUAGGAGUUGUGUUCCAAGUUUGUUCCUGCAAACCCUCCGAUGAGGCCAGCUGCAUUCAUCGGGGCCUGGAUGGCCGCACCUCUCUCUCCCCGCCCUGUCUCCUGCACUCAGGUGAGAGGCUGGCAGGGCUGCCGUAGGGGUGGAGAGUGAACGCAGGGUGGCUAAGCCCUCGUCCCUGUGAGGGACAGUGACACGGAUGGGAGCAGCCAUCUGAGCUGGAAGCUGUGGACAUGGUCCUUGUGUGGGUCCAAGCAAAGUGGGUGGCGUGUGCAUUUUGUGAACACGUGGUCUGCUUCCUGGUGCAGACCAGGUCUCCCCAGAGGGACCCUCCUGAGCUGAGCUGCCCGGGGCACCUGUCCCUGGAUGUGAACUGCCUUGGUUGUACCUUGGUGGGGGGACCUUUCCUGAAUGUGUUGGUUCGGCAUGGUGACAGGUGUUUCCCUGCGGCAGAAUGUUGGGGCCACACCAACGUCCCCAGAGUCUUCUCCCUAGAGUCUCUGAAAGGAAGCCUGGGUUCCUGGUGGUGCUCCCCUCCAUGUGUGCUCACCCGCCUGUAUGGAGGCAGCCCAGGGGAGCGGCUGAGACUCUUGGCAGAGAGCUGGGGACGCUCUGUUCUCAUUGGCAGCCCCACCCUGAAGAAUAACAGACUCCCAAAUAUCACACAGGCUGCAGAUACCACCCAGCCCCCAAGGAUGCCAUCACCAGGCUGGGGCGCUCCCAUGCCCAUUAUCCAGGGGUAAUUUUUGCUCACUUAUUUAUAAGCCACACAUCCUCUUCUAUCCUACCAAACCUAAGAAUAUCAAAAGGGAAAGCUUGGCUUGCAUGGACGUAAUUAACCUAAAAGUCUUUAAACGUUUCUCCCGAGUGUUGGAGUGACUGUUUGCACACAUCUGUUGUGUUUUGCCUGUGUGCAUUCCUCCUCCUGGUCAGAGAGCCCGUCUCUUCCGCCCUCUCCCUUACCCUAGGAGGGCUGAGUCAGGCCUCCCUACCCAGGCCCAAGGGCAGAUGCACCUGAGCCAUUGUGUCCCAUGGUUGAUACGGGACGGGGCUGAUUUCCUGACCUGGACCCCUGAGACCCAGUGCUCUUAGCUGUGAGCCUCUGGGAAGAGGUUCUGGCAGGUGGAGGGGAUGGACGUUACAGUGCUGUGGCCACCUAGAAAAGCCGUCCCGGAACUGAGACCAACUGCUGAGGGAGGAAGGGCCACCAGAUCGGGGGCCGGGCCGGGGUGAGCACCUGAAGCCGGCUCCACCUGCUCUUCUCAGCUGUGCGCCUCCAGGAAUUUGCACUCGCUUCAGCUGAUUUGGGUUGGAUUUCUAGCGUUUCACAUACAGGAUCUAGACUCGCACACAACUGCAUUAAUAUGUUGGUGUUUGAUAAACUAGGGUUGAAGGAGUUCCAUCAGUGAAGAGAGAAGCCACGUGACCUGAGGAUGCAGGGCACUGUUCACGUGGACAUGAGCCGUUUCUUAGCAUCAUGAGAUUUUAGAAACAUGUUCUUACUCUGCCAGGACCCAGGGAUAGGUGAGGCUCUCCUAUUGGGAUACCAUUUCACCAGCAGAGAGAUUAAUUGGAGAAUGUGUAAUUUUUUCCCCUUUGGAAAUAAUUUGUUCUUUUUUUUUUUUGACAGAGUUUCUUUCUGUCAUCCAGGCUGGAGUGCAGUGGUGUGAUCAUAGCUCACUGCAGCCUCGACCUCCUGGGCUCAAGUGGUCCUCCCACCUCAGCCUCCCAAGUAGCUGGGACUACAGGCAUGCACCACCAUGCCCGGCUAAUUUUUACAUUUUUGGUAGAGGCCGGGUACGGUGGCUCAUGCCUGUAAUCCCGGCACUUUGGGAGGCCGAGGUGGGUGGAUCACGAGGUCAGGAGAUCAAGACCAUCCUGGAUAACAUGGUGAAACCCCGUCUCUACUAAAAUACAAAAAAAUUAGCCGGGCGUGGUGGUGGGCGCCUGUAGUCCCAGCUACUCGGGAGGCUGAGGCAGGAGAAUGGCGUGAACCCGGGAGGCGGAGCUUGCAGUGAGCGGAGAUUGGCGCCACUACACUCCAGCCUGGGCGACAGAGCGAGACUCCGUCUCAAAAAAAAAUUUUUUUUUUUGGUAGAUACGGGGUCUUGCUUUGUCACCCAGGCUGGUCUCAAACUCCUGAGCUCGAGUGCUCCUUCUGCCUCAGCCUCCCAAAGUGCUGGGAUUACAGGCGUGGGCUGCUGUGCCCAGCAGGAAUAAUUUCUCAGUGCAUCUCUGAUGGGGAGGCUAAUGAAGAAAGGACACCUGGUUUGAAGGCUUCUCUGUGUCUGUCCGUGGGCGCUACUGAUCUGAGCCAAGCACCAUUCCGCAGGCAUGCCUGAAAUGACUCCCAUGGCUGUCAUGGUGCCAUCUGGAGAGCAUUUGCUCACUGUAAUGGUCCCGUCACACUUGUCUGAUGAGGAUCUGUUGGUUGACUUUGACAGUGAUAAACGAACACAGCCUAUCUGGGUGUUUUUUGCACUUAUAGUUUGGGGGUUUGAAGUACUGGCUAGAAGCUGGCGGGGUGUGUGUGUGCAGGUGUGCGAGUGCAUGUGCAAGUGUGCGUGCAAGUGUGAGUCUGCACUUGUGUGCAAGAGAAUGUGUGUGUGUGUGUGUUUGGAGAUUUGGACUUGAAAAUUCUAGCUCAGGUCUUUGGGGUAGUGUUUGACCUGAACUCUGAAAGGCAGAGGGUCCCAGACUUUCCUGGGAUGAUGGGAACUGGGCACCCCAGAUGAGGCUCGGUUGUGAGUAGGAGCGGGGUGGGCCACCGAAGAGAAGACAGAGUGGGCCUGUAGGGCCAGCCCGAGGUACCCACAGUGGAGGGUCUACAGGCUGAUUUGGGAGGUGGUGGUUUAUACCUGUAGUCACCUUCUAUCUUAGUUAGGAAUUCACCUUCACACUUCCAGAAACUGCCAAGAAGAAUGCCGCCGCUCAGGUUUAUCUGGUAGAAUAAGCUGUUUGAACAAAGAUCUGGAGGUUGCACAAUCCUGUGUCAUUCUGGAUUUAUCUUGGGGUCGGGAGUCAACGAUACUUCUUGUGCUGUCGUUUCUCCGGCCGUGUGAAGUUACCACCUCGUGAGUGGUCAUAAGUUAGCGUGUCUAAAUGCACUUUGAAAUCCUAGGAUGAAAAAGCCAGGCCCUGUCUUUUUUCCUUGUCUAAGCACCAUCCUUGCUUAGGAGAGACACGGCUGUGGCUCUCAGGCUGUGGGGCAAUGUUCUGCUUAUAAUGUUUCAAGAGGUUCAAAGCGUGCAGGCCCCAUGCUCCGUGAGAGCCUUGACCUGGGUCAGCAGGGGCGGCUGGGCUUGACUCGAGAAUUCCCACAGGGCCCGAGGGAAGAGCAGAGCAAGAGGGAGGAGCGCGUGGAGCCCUAUGUGGCCUGCGAUAUUGGGGUGGCGUCCAGGCCCGCCUAGAUGGGGGAGGGAGACAACAGAGCUGCCACCUGCUCACCGCAGACCCAGGGGCCCAGGAGGAGCGGACUAGGACCGGCAGUGCCUUCCAGCCUAGGUCUCCUGCCCCUGGGCUGGAGUUCAUCUUUUAGGCAAAUUUGGAAUAGGAACCUUAAAAAUGCUUUCUUCACUCGUUUAAAUAGUAAUGAUAAGAAUAUGGCUGCAGGGGGCAGCUUAUGCCUGUAAUCCCACCAUUUUGGGAGCUCAAGGCAGGAGUAUUGCUUGAGCCCAGAAGUUUGAGACCAGUCUGGGCAACAUAGUGGAAACUUGUCUCUCCAAAAGCUAAAAGAAAAAGCCGUGCAUGGUGGUAUGCACCUGUAGUCCCAGCUACUUGGGAGGCUGAGGUGGGAGGAUCGCUUGAGUCUGGGAGGUCGAGGCUGCUGUGAGCCAUGAUUGCACCACUGCAUUCCAGCCUGGGUGACAGAGCAAGAUCUUGUCUUAAAAAAAAAAAAAAAAAAAAAGGUGUUGUAUUUUAUCAUUAGAAGGCCAUCCUGUUUAGAAGAGUGGGUUUCUCAUAAGAAAAAAAAGAAAAAGGUUGACCUUGUAAGUAUAUUUUCUUGGGUGAAUUGUGGUGGUGGUAAUGGUUUUAACUGGUGUUAAUUUCAGUUCUUUUAAAAGUUGUGGUAAGAUACAUGCAACAUAAAAUGUGCCCUCUUCCCCAUUUUUAAGUGAACAGUUCAGUGGCAUUAAGCACAUUCAGUUUGCCUGCCACCGUUACCACCAUCCAUCUCCAAAAUUCUCUCCAUUUACAAAACUGAAACUCUGUCCCUAUUAAACACUAGCUCCCCAUUCCCCACUGUGCCGCCCCCCCAAAGCCCCUGGCACCAACCAUUCUACUUCCUGUCUCUGAGUUUGACUAGGGACCUCCUGUAAGUGGAUUUGUACAAUAUUUGUCCUUUUGUGUCUGGCUUCUUCAUGUAGUAUAAUGUCUUCAAGGUUCAUUCAUGUUGUAGUCAGGAUCACCUUCCUUUUAAAGGUUGAACGAUAUCCCGUUGUAUGGACAGACCACAUUUUAUCCAUUCACCCAGGGAUGGACACCUGGGUUGCUUCCAUCUCUCGGCUCUUGUGAAUAAUGCUGCUGUGAACACGGGUGUGCAGAUACCUGUUCAAGUCCCUGCUGUUUUCUUUUGAGACGGAGUCUCGCUCUGUCUCCCAGGCUGGAGUGCGGUGGCACCAUCUCAGCUCACUGCAAGCUCCGCCUCCCAGGUUCAGGCCAUUCUCCUGCCUCAGCCUCCCGAGUAGCUGGGACUACAGGUGCCCACCACCACGCCUGGCUAAUUUUUUGUAUUUUUAGUAGAGACGGAGUUUCACCAUGUUAGCCAGGAUGCUCUGGAUCUCCUGACCUCGUGAUCCACCCACCUCGGCCUCCCAAACUGCUGGGAUUACAGGCAUGAGACACCACGCCCCGCCGAGUCCCUGCUUUUAAUUCUUUGGGGCAGGGAUCCCCAACCCCCUGGUGAUGGACCAAUACUGGCCUGCGGCCCCUUAGGAACUGGACUGCACAGCAGGAGGUGAGCGGCAGGUGAGCGUGCAUUCCCGCCGGAGCCCCGCCUCCCGUCAGAUCAGCGGCGGCAUUAGAUUCUCAUAGGAGCGGGAACCCUCCUGUGAACCCUGCAUACCAGGGUUCUCCAUGCAACAAUCUAAUGCCUGAUGAUCUGAAGUGGAACAGGUUUUUGUUUUUUUUUUCCAGACAGAGUCUUGCUCUUUCGCCUAGGCUGGAGUGCAGUGGCAUGAUCUCGGCUCACUGCAACCCCUGCUUCCUGGGUUCAAGUGGUUCUCCUGCCUCAGCCUCCCAAGUAGCUGGGAUUACAGGUGCCCGCCACCAUGGCCAGCUAAUUUUUUUGUUUAUUUGUUUAUUUAUUAUUUUUUGAGGUGGAGUCUUGCUGUCACCCAGGCUGGAGUGCAGUGGUGCAAUCUCAGCUCACUGCAACCUCUGCCUUCUGGGUUCAAGCCAUUCUUGUGCCUCAGCUUCCCGAGUAGGUGGAAUUAUAGGCGUGUGCCACCAUGCCCAGCUAAUUUUUGUAUUUUUAGUAGAGGCGGGAUUUCACCAUGUUGGCCAGGCUGGUCUCACUCUUGACCUCAAGUGAUCUGCCCGCCUCGGCCUCCCAAAGUGUUGGGAUUACAGGUGUGAGCCACCGUGCUCAGCCUGAAGUGAAACAGUUUCAUCCCAAAAGCAUAUACCUCUGCCCCAUCCAUGGAAAAAUUGCCUCUCAUGAAACCAGUCCCUGGUGCCAAAAAGGUUGGGGACCGCGGCUCUGGAGUAUAUGCCUAGGAGUAGGAGUGUGGGGUCAUAUGGUAAUUUAUCUUUAAUUUUUGGAGGAAUUGAAUUUCAAUUCUUAUUAUUACCAAAAAUACUUAAAAUUCUUACAGAUGGCAUGGGAAAGUAGCACACAGUCGGGACUCUGCAGCCGAGUUUGCCUCCUUGAAUGCACACAUAACACAGGAACAAAGACAGAGCUGCUUCCCUCCUGUUGGGUCUCUGGCGGACAGUCAGGUAUGCUGAGGGAGACACUGUUCUCAAACUCCAGGCCAGGGUGGUUUCCGGAGGGUCCACCGGUGGUCUCAUCUCUUCUCUCUCAAACCAUGGAUGGUGCCUUUUAAAGAAAAUGACACCGGCCAGGUGCGGUGGCUCAUGGCUGUAAUCCCAGCACUUUGGGAGGCCGAGGCGGGUGGAUCACCUGAGGUCGGAAGUUCAACACCAGCCUGGCCAACAUGGUGAAACCCCGUCUCUAUUAAAAAUACAAAAAUUAGGCCGGGCGCGGUGGCUCACGCCUGUAAUCCCAGCACUUUGGGAGGCCGAGGCGGGCGGAUCACGAGGUCAGGAGAUCGAGACCAUCCCGGCUAAAACGGUGAAACCCCGUCUCUACUAAAAAUACAAAAAAUUAGCCGGGCGUAGUGGCGGGCGCCUGUAGUCCCAGCUACUUGGGAGGCUGAGGCAGGAGAAUGGCGUGAACCCGGGAGGCGGAGCUUGCAGUGAGCCGAGAUCCCGCCACUGCACUCCAGCCUGGGCGACAGAGCGAGACUCCGUCUCAAAAAAAAAAAAAAAAAAAAAAAAAUACAAAAAUUAGCUGGGUGUGGUGGUGGGCACCUGUAAUCCCAGCUACUGAGGAGGCUGAGGCAUGAGAUUCGCUUGAGCCUGGGAGGCAGAGGUUGCAGUGAGCUGAGAUCGCGCCAUUGCACUCCAGCCUGGGCAACAGAGUGAGACUCUGUCUCAAAAAACAAACAAAAAUCAAAGUGCCAACCUCUGGGCUGUCCCCUCCUGGCCUGCCUUGUUCCUGAGCUCACCAGGGUCCUUCACUCUGUGGCACUGGCCUCAGCCAGCACCAAGGCUGAAAGAGCCCAUUCAGAGGCCAGAAAGAAACUGUUAGGCUCUGAAGCCGUGGGCCAGGCCAAGACAGAGAUUCUGAGGCAUGGUUCUGGAAUGGGUUUUUCCGCCCACAGGCACUCAAGGAGGACAGCAUUGGGAGAUGGCUGGGUGGAGAGUCUGCGGGAGGCUACAAGGCAAAAAUCCCCUACUCCCCCUGGGCUCCUUCACAGUUUGUGUGUCCUCACAGAGCAAGGAAGUUCUGUGAGCCUCAUUCAAUCAUCUGAGGUUCUUCCCAGGAAAAUUAUAGUGGGAACUCUGGCUUUGAUGAAACUGCUUUUUUUUCAAAGCAGUUUGCAAAAUAACCGGGGCCUUAAAAAACAAUCUGGAUGAAAUGGUUUUUGCCAUUUCAAUUGGUUCUCUUCCAACGUGUCUUCCUUCCAGUAGGUUUCCAGAAUAUUUUGGUUUCAAAAUUUGGGGGCACAGAUUUGCAAAGUGGAUUUCAACAUGUCGGGUUUCAAAGGGGGCUGGCUUUGAAAGUGGUCUGGGCUUCUAAAAGGUUUGAUUGAAAACUGGUUUGGUUCUCAGACAUUCCAGAAGCUUCUCCCGGAGUCCAGAGCCUCCCAGUGGUGCUUUGGGAAGGGGGCCAGGCAGGGCGUCCUGGUGAGUGGACGUAGGGUGGGCAGGGCCACCCUUGUCCUGGGAUGUUGUGGAGGACUUGGCACGCCCUGUCUCAGGCCUGGCUCUGGCUCUGGGUGGAUGUUUUGCAUCUUCAGAAAAAAGCUCCUGUGGGAUAUUUCUCCUCCAGCCGACCCCGCCCCCCAGGGCAUUCGAGAAAAGGGUGCUUGUCUCUUGGUGAGAGGGCCACGGUUCCUUCAGUUUCUCCGUUCCUACGGGCCUCUUUCUUUUUCCUUUUUGAGACGGAAUCUCACUGUGUCGCCCAGGCUCACUGCAACCUAUGCCUCCCGGGUUCAAGUGGUUCUCAUGCUUCAGCCUCCUGAGUAGCUGGGAUUACAGGUGUGUGCCACCACAUCCAGCUAAUUUUUUGUAUUUUUAGUAGAGAUGGGGUUUUCCCAUGUUGGCCAGGCCGGUCUCGAACUCCUGACCUCGUGAUCUGCCCACGUUGGCCUCCAAAGUGCUAGGAUUAUAAGUGUGAGCCACCACACCAGGCCCGUUUCAUCCCUGCCUCAGCCUGCAUGCCAAGCUCCCUGGGUGCCCGCCCACAGGUGUCACCCUUUAAGGAGAAAGUGGCCUGGGGCUGGAAACAGGACUUUGUAGGGAAGGACAGCGCGUGUGAGAAAAGGCCUGUUGAUGGGCACGCCAGGGUUUAAUGGACGGCUCUUUGAAGUCAUGGGCUGAGCCAGAAGGAAUUGUCAUGAUGUCAGUCUCAUUUCCAGAUGGGGAAAGGGAGACCCAGGCUGCGGUGACCCACUGAGGCACAGGAUCAGUGAGAACCCAGCCCUGGCUUUGCCCAGACCUCUCAAGGGCACUUCGUGGGACCAUUGCCGGCCGUUGUGGCAUCUGUCCCUGGCCUUGCCCCCAUCCGUCUCUGCACAGCCCAGGUGGGUCCGAGCCAGCCCCAGGUCUCCAGGGUCCCAGCCCAGCCUCUAGAAGAGCCAGCAGCAGGGCUGGAAGGGAGAGCACAUGCUGGGCCUUGGGGCUGCCUUGGACCUCAGGCCGUUGACAAGGAAAAGCGGAGAGUUGGGAAAAAAGGACAAAUAGCUGAGCGCCAGCCGCAGUCUGGGGGACGGGAGCCUCGUGCGACUCUCGGAGUGCUGGCCAGAUUGGCAGAGGGGAGGAGAGAGGAAAAACCCAGGCUCUGAGGAAAAACCUCUCCAGCCCAGCGCGUGGCCUGGCAUUAACCCACUGCAGCCCCAGGAAGUGGUUCCACCCCAGGCAGCCAACAAGGCGGUGCCUGAACUAUGUCUGUGGAUGACGGAGCCACGACCUGUCCCUCAGGGCUCAGCGCUGCGGCUAUGUCCAGGGACCCCUGGCUGUGCCCACGUCGGGGCUUCCCGUUCCUUACCUGCCAUGAGAAUGAGAUGUCCAGGGACCUCCCUGCUCCAGCUGGGACCUGUGGGGCUUUGUCUGUUGUCCCGAGCACCUUGGAGAUGUCAUUUCUAACAUUUUAACCCAGGAAUCCCCCCACCAAGGGACAGAGUGCAAGGACAUGAUCGAACAGAAAAAGUUCUGGUACAAGAUCAACCCCGUGGGGUGGUGAGUGCUGCAGCCCCGGGCCUCACAUCCUGCCGUCCCUGUGGGAGAUUGGAGCGGUCCCAGUGCCCACCGCUGAUUCUCUGGCUCCAGCAACCCCUCCAGGUGGAUCCGUCCCACGCAGCCUGGCCUGAAACACUGCCCAGCCACUGGGUCCAGUAAGACAGAGCCUCGAGUCAUUCUGCCAAGAGGAUCCAGAAACACAGACUUUUUCUGGGGUCCUGGAGGCUUCUGGCCCAUGGGGAGCCCCUGGGUCCCAGCGAUCCAGCCCUGAUGUGCUGAGGGUGCAGGGCCCAGCUGCAGAGCAGAGGAGAGUGGCCCCCAGGGACCAGCAGCACGAAAGGCACACUGAGGCACACUGGCAGGCCUGGGCUGCAGAGAGCCUGAAGGUCAUGGGGUAGCUGGUGGAAGCAGGAAGACCCCAUACAGCAGCGACCACUGAGGCUGGUGCUGCACUUUCUCAGGGAAUUGAGUGUGGGCUCCCACCAUCCCGGCCACUGGCUUCCUCCAAAGCCUCCUCCUCUUACAUCAGCAAACCUUCUGUUCGGUGACCCCCUCAGUGACCCUCUGUGCUUGCCUUCGUGGUCUUCCUCAUGGAGGAUUUCGGGUCAGCGUGGGGGUCAGAGGUCAUUUCCCAUACCCCCUCAAAGGUACUUCUUGCUGUGGUCCCCACACUCUGACACCCUCUUCUGAAAUGAACACUUUUUUGUUGUUGUUGUUGAGACAGAGUCUUGCUCUGUCGCCCAGGCUGGAGUGCAGUGGCACAAUCUUAGCUCACUGCAACCUCCACCUCCCAGGUUCAAGCGAUUUUCAUGCCUCAGCUUCCCGAGUAGCUGGGAUUACAGGCAUGUGCCACCAAGCCCAGCUAAUUUUUGUAUUUUUAGUAGAGAUGAGGUUUCACCAUGUUGGCCAGGCUGGUCUCGAACUUCUGACCUCAAGUGAUUCGCCCGCCUCGGCCUCCCAAAGUGCUGGGAUUACAAGCAUGAGCCACUGCGCCCGGCCACAAACACUUUUUUUUUUUUAAACAAGUGAAAACAAGUUUAUUAACAAAGUUAAGAAAUAAAGAAUGGCUAUUCCAUAGGGAGAGCAGCCUGAAUAAACACUUUUUUUGUUGUUGUUGAGGCAGAGCCUCACUCUGUCGCCCAGGCAGGAGUGCAGUGGUGCGACCUCAGCUCUCAGCUCCCUGCACCGUCCACCUCCUGGGUUCAAGCGCUUCUUCCCCAAGUAGCUGGGACUAUAGGCACACACCACCAUGCCCGGCUAAUUUUUCUCUUUUUAGUAGAGACAGGAUUUCGCCAUGUGGGUCGGGCUGGUCUCGAACUCCUGGUCUCAAGUGAUCCGCCCUCCUCGGCCUUCCAAAAUGCUAGGAUUACAGGCAUGAGCCGCCGUGCCUGGCCACAAACAUAUUUUAAAUUUGAACAAUAAAGGAACUGGACCAGGAAGUGUGGAGUUGGGGAGACCCUGCUCUCGCCAGGUGCCUUCCCGGCAGGUUGUCUCUGCCUCCCCUUGCACCCCUUGAAUGGCGGGCUCCCUCUCCCAUAGCCCCUGCCAGGCUGGAUAACCAACUUCAUUCUUAUACCCGUCCGAAUCUGCCCCCUGUUAAUGGCACCCACCAGUCCUUGUCCAAACCUCGAAGCUCAGGACCUCACAGAGCACCACGUCCUCUUCUGUGUCAUAUGCAGCUGGAUCUCAGUAAAUGGCAAUGUCUUCUCUA